GACUCAGGCCCAGGGCGCUGCCCGGGUGGCCGCGGCGCUGGACGACGGCUCGGCCCUUGGCCGCUUCGAGCGGAUGCUGGCGGCGCAGGGCGUGGAUCCCGGUCUGGCCCGAGCCCUGUGCUCGGGAAGUCCCGCAGAACGCCGGCAGCUGCUGCCUCGCGCCCGGGAGCAGGAGGAGCUGCUGGCGCCCGCAGAUGGAGCAUCAGAUCCAUGCUGCUGCUGACUCGGAGCCCCACAGCUUGGCACAGGCUCUCUCAGCUCAAGCCUCGGGUCCUCCCUGGGACCCUGGGAGGCCAGGCCCUGCAUCUGAGGUCCUGGCUUUUGUCAAGGCAGGGCCCUGCAGAGACAGGUGGGCAGGGCCAGCCCCAGGGCCCUGGGCUUCGAACCCGGCUGCUGAUCACAGGCCUGUUCGGGGCUGGACUCGGUGGGGCCUGGCUGGCCCUGAGGGCUGAGAAGGAGAGGCUGCAGCAGCAAAAGCGAACAGAAGCCCUGCGCCAGGCAGCUGUGGGCCAGGGCGACUUCCACCUGCUGGAUCACAGAGGCCGGGCUCGCUGCAAGGCUGACUUCCGGGGCCAGUGGGUGCUGAUGUACUUUGGCUUCACUCACUGCCCUGACAUCUGCCCAGACGAGCUGGAGAAGCUGGUGCAGGUGGUGCGGCAGCUGGAAGCAGAGCCUGGUUUGCCUCCAGUGCAGCCUGUCUUCAUCACUGUGGACCCCGAGCGGGACGACGUUGAAGCCAUGGCCCGCUACGUCCAGGACUUCCACCCAAGACUGUUGGGUCUGACCGGCUCCACCAAACAGGUUGCCCAGGCUAGUCACAGUUACCGCGUGUACUACAAUGCAGGCCCCAAGGAUGAGGACCAGGACUACAUCGUGGACCACUCCAUUGCCAUCUACCUGCUCAACCCUGACGGCCUCUUCACGGAUUACUACGGCCGGAGCAGAUCGGCUGAGCAGAUCUCAGACAGUGUGCGGCGGCACAUGGCGGCUUUCCGCAGUGUCCUGUCUUGAGCCACUGCAGUCUGGGCCCCAUCAUUAAACGGGCUGCGUUUAA